CUGUCGGGGCUGGAGCUGGGCAUAUGGGGAAACUGGGGGACCGGCACGGGUUCCAGGCGAGUGGACGGUGGGAUGGAAUCCGACGUGCACACCCAUGUCUCAGGCUUUGUUUGAUGGAGGCUACUGUUUCCACCUCAUGUCGCCGCCCCUUUGCUUAUGGACUCUUGCAGAGUUGGAUUGAGCUCGGGCUGUGUGAUAUAGUGGUUGUUGCAGAAGCCCCAGGGCCACUUUCUGACUAGUACCUUGGGCACCUGACAUCAUCCCUUUGAGUCUCAGUGUCCUCUUCUUUAAAGUGAGGGCGCUCUACCUGAGGAGAUUGCUGUAAGGUUGGAAUGAACCUGCAUGUGUGUGUCAUGUGGGAAGGGAACAGUCAGUGGGGCCUGGGGUUCUCUUGGAGAGCUGGUAACCAGCCUCGUCCCUGAGGCAACAGCCAGAGGGCGCCUGUAGUUUCCCCACGCAUGUCUGUUAGCAGUUACGGCCUCUGGAGGAUCUCCUGUGGGAGGUCCCUACUUCUCACUACAAUCUUUAGAGACUUUGGAGGAUUUCCUAUGGAAGGUCCCCACUUCUCACCACAACAUUCUGGGUUAAAAUGGCCUUGGUAGGGGGAUGGGGGCUGAAGCUGGAUUUUUUUGCUUGCAUUACAAGCUUCUGAACCAAGGACUUCAUGUCACCUGGACUUGGAUUCACAUCCCAGCUCCUUCCUCUCCUAGCUCUAGGACUGUGUAACCUUGGGCAAAUCUCUUAACCUCUUUAAGCCUUAAUUGUUUCAUCUGUAAAAUGAGGCUAACAGUACCUACCUUCCACAAUUGUCGAGAAUUAAAUCAGACAUUGUAGGUAGAGCACUUAAUAGUUGGCAUUCAGCGGCAGCAGUUACUGUUAUGUUAGCAUGUGGAGUGUCUGAGUGUGUGCACAUUGGCUCGAACAGCCUUUUGACAGUGGCACAGUUGGUGCUUGUGUAAGACAGCAGGGCAGAGAAGUCAAAGCCCUCGGUUUUCUAGUCAAACUGGUGGGCCACAACAGUGGUGACCUAAGUCUAAUGAAUCUUCAACUGAACAAGGCAGAUUGAAUCUCCAGGUGAGGACCAAGAGUCUGGGGAUCAGCUGCCUCCACAUUUUUGGGCAUAGAAGGCUGUACAAUACCGCCUUUGUUGUAAGAGCAAGGAACCAUUCAGGGAAGGCACCAUGUGGUAAGGAAUAGAGGCCAGACGUGGAUUAAGAACAAAACAAGAGAAUAGUGUUUGUCUUUAAGUGGAGCCUUGGACUCAAAACAGGAUCUGAGCCCUGAGGAUUUUUUUUUUUUUAAUUGAGAUGGAGUCUUCGUCUGUCACCCAGGCUGGAGUGCAGUGGCGCGAUCUCAGCUCACUGCAACCUCCUUCCCCUGGGUUCAAGCGAUUCUCGUGUCUCAGCCUCCCUAGUAGCUGGGAUUACAGGUGGCUGCCACCACACUCGGCGAGUUUUUUGUAUUUUUAGUGGAAACGGGGUUUCACCACGUUGGCCAGGCUGGUCUUGAACUCCUGACCUCAAGUGAUCCACCCACCUCGGCCUCCCAAAUUGUUAGGGAUAUCACGCAUGAGCCACUACAACUGGCCCUUGUGGGAAGGCACAGCCAUGUCUCCUGAAGUUAACAAGCACUAAGCUUUCCCAAGUAGUGAAAUGUCAAGCCCCUGCUUCUGUCACUUAUUUGUUCAUUCAGCAGAAAGUCACUGAGAGCCUUCUGUGCACCAGGCACAGUGCUGGGCAGUGAAAGAGACAGACAUGUGCCCUGGACCCAGGGAGAUGACAAGUGAUGGCUGUCAGGCCCAGACCCUGUUGUUUGUCUGCAGCCUCUUCCCUCAGGCAACUUGUUCUCUAUCAGGAGAAACGAAAUAAUUAUUAUCUGGAGAGGCAGGUGGGGGCGCUGCUCCUAGAAGACUGGGACAGCCUGGUAGAGGUUCUAGCUUGAUCAUGUGAGCAGUGGAAACCAUUUUAAGUAGGAGGUUAACAGGACCAAAAUAGCAUUUAAAAAAUUGUUUAUGGCCACUGUGAAGCCAGUUUCACCAGCGUCACUUGCCCAUGCUGGGCUGCCACCCAGCUAAUUCCUGGUCCUGCUCAUUUAGCCCAGCUCAGCUCACAUCACUUCCUCCAGAAACUAGAGAAGGGUAGAGCCCCUGACCAUCUUCACAGCAUUAGUCCUGAUAGCUGAAUCUUACGUCAGUUGUUAACAUCUGUGACCUGUGCAGGGAGAAUGGCAGGGCUGAGUUUCACCUACAUUGUUUCCCCAAUACCUACAGCAGAGCCAAGCACAGUGGGAACUUUCAGAAAGCACUGGUUGAAGGAACGCUGGAAUCCCUGGGACUUACUGCGUAGCAUGUAGUAGUUGCUCCUCUAGAAAAGUUUCACCUUAUGAAGUAUAGCAGGCUCUGAUGCUGGUGUCUGGUAGAAGAAGGUUACUCACAGUUCUGCUGCAGGCUCAGAAGUGGCCCUUUCAACCCUCCAGAGACAUGAGACUAGUGCAGUUCCGGGCACCCCACCUGGUGGGGCCUCACUUGGGCCUGGAGACAGGGAAUGGUGGAGGGGUUAUCAACCUCAAUGCCUUUGACCCCACACUCCCGAAGACGAUGACGCAGUUCCUAGAGCAGGGAGAGGCCACCCUCUCAGUGGCAAGAAGAGCCCUGGCUGCCCAGUUGCCAGUCCUACCACGGUCGGAGGUAACCUUCCUGGCUCCAGUCACACGACCAGAUAAGGUGGUGUGUGUGGGCAUGAAUUAUGUGGACCACUGCAAAGAACAGAACGUGCCCGUGCCCAAGGAGCCCAUCAUCUUCAGCAAGUUUGCCAGCUCCAUCGUGGGGCCCUAUGAUGAGGUGGUCCUCCCACCACAGAGCCAGGAGGUAGAUUGGGAAGUGGAGCUGGCCGUGGUCAUUGGAAAGAAAGGCAAGCACAUCAAGGCCACAGAUGCUAUGGCCCACGUGGCCGGCUUCACUGUGGCUCAUGACGUGAGUGCUCGUGACUGGCAAAUGAGACGUAAUGGGAAACAAUGGCUGCUGGGAAAAACCUUCGACACCUUCUGCCCUCUGGGCCCUGCCUUGGUGACCAAGGACAGUGUAGCAGAUCCACACAACUUAAAGAUCUGCUGCCGAGUGAAUGGGGAAGUGGUCCAGAGCGGCAACACCAACCAGAUGGUAUUCAAGACAGAGGACCUGAUAGCCUGGGUCUCCCAGUUUGUUACCUUUUACCCAGGGGAUGUCAUCCUAACUGGGACCCCCCCAGGUGUCGGUGUAUUCAGGAAACCUCCUGUCUUUCUCAAGAAGGGGGAUGAAGUCCAGUGUGAGAUUGAAGAACUAGGUGUCAUCAUCAACAAGGUGGUGUGAUGGCUCCUGCACAGGCCCUGCACAUAGGAUGAGGGCAUCUGCUCCCACUCAGCCUAGCCCAGGGAAAGGCCCAGUGACAGGUGUGGACAGGUGCCAGCCCUGCAAGCCGCCUCUUCUCGGUAGAAGGGAGAAGGACAGAGCUCUCUUCAAUAAAUUCGUCAGGUCAAAGCAGCAGCUUUGCUUCUGCUGUUUGUCUUCUUUUGGGCUUUGUUUCAUGGGACAAGUUGGGGCAUUUUGUGGGACUGGGGAAGAAGAGAGCAAAUACACACACAUAUGCCAAAAAGAUGCUGCUGGGCUGGGGAAAAGACAAUUCGUGUCGUCCCCUUGUUUAUCACAUCAAAGAAGGGAAAAAGCAAGAGAUGGCAAGGGACAAUCAAGCCUCAAUGAUUAUAUUUAUAGCUAAGGGUUUGCAGCCUCCUCUCCAUCUUCUGGCUCUAGGACACAGCUGUGUUCUGGGGCUCAGAAGUCUCAGCACAGGCUCCUUCUCACAGUUCUAGCUACAAGUGAACUGCCGGAUGAACUGUUCUAGUUUUUCCUGAUUGUCCAGGCUGGCAAAAGUAGGGGACAGGUGGAGCCUGGGGCCUGCAGGGCUCGGCGUCUGCUGCAGAACCUGGGCCAUGGAAGAUGGGCCGUGAGUGCACUCACCACAGGGACUGUGUCCACAUGGCCCAGGGGCCAGGCCUGUCCCCCAGAAACCUGCCUUGAGACCUCUGACCCCUUAGGCCUCAGUGUUUGAGUGCAAAUGCUGCCUCAAAGCAGCCCCAAUACCCCACCUAGAAGGAUGAGCCAGUGAUUUGGGAGACCAAGAGGCAGGAAACCAUCCCACCUUCUCCAACCCAUCACCACGUCUAUUGCUGGAAGACACCAAGUAAAUCCCAGGGUCUUAAUGAGGCACCAUCAGGCCAGCCCUGUGGGGUGAUGGGAACAUAGCUGGGUUUCCCUGAGCCACUCUAUUGGGGUGGGAGCAGGGGGACAGAAGAUGGUGACACUGGCUCCUCUCACCCCUAGGUCUCUGAAGGUCCAGAUAGCACUGAUGGCAAGCUUUGGGUCUGCACACUCUGGAAAGAAGAGAGAAGUGAAGGCUCUAGGUAGGGAGGACAGGGAGACACUGGGCACAGGCUUCUCUCCUCUUGUUUAAAGAAGCCCAGGGAGGGAUAGAUCUCCGACUGGACAGAAGACUACUCUGCAGCCCGCCUUCCUAGAGUUGGGUUGUCACUGUCCGGCAGGGGGCAGCAGCCACCAGCAAACACCACUGCCUGCAGGAGCCUGGGCUGACUGGUUGGGACUCACCAAAGAUCCCUUCUUCCUGGGCGGUGGCCUGCAGGAACUGGAACAGCUGUUGGAGAGGAGAAGAAAAAGAAGACAUCAAAAAGAAAAUCUAGUGCUGGGUGGAUAUAGAGUAUGAAGAUGUGGAGCUGGGAAAACAGAGGAUGUGGUGGGAUGGGGAAGGAAAGGUUGUGGAAGGCCUGCACCCCGUCUCAGUUCCUCCACUGCUUCGUCCCAGAUUCUGUUUUUGUUUUCCUGAAUCAGACUUAGUCUCCCUCCAUUCUCCCGUCCCCUGUGUGCCCCCAUCCUGGUCCUGCCUCACUGGACAGCCUCUCCGCGGCCUUCCUCCUCCCUGCUCCAGAAUUCUACUUGGUGCCCCCCAACCCCACUCGACUCAUUGUCCACCUGGCCUCUGAGGCCAGGCACCCUCAUUCCCCUCUCCCACCCACCCCACCCAAGGAAGCCCAGCACAGACCAUCUCAUCUCACUCCACCAUCACUUCUUUGCCAAAUGCAUUUCCAAACACCCUCAUGAGCUUUGCUGAUCUCUUUGCCAUCUCUCCCUGCCCCACUCCGAUGGCUCCUCCUGCCUGGUGAAGACUGCCCUGGGUAUCCCAGAACUGAACCUGCAGCAGCCAGCACAGCUGACCUUGGGGCGAUAAGCAGCCAGGGAAAGGCUUUCUUAAAAAAAAACAAAAAACAAAACCAAUAACUCAGUAAGCAGAUUAAACAAAGGUAGAGACGGAGCCCUCCACCCCUCUCACACACUCAUCCUCACACCCAGCUAUACCACACCCCACAAAUGUUGCUUAUGUUUCCUUGGUCAUUCUGUCCAUCCUCCUGUCUGUCCAAAGCCAAGGACACUGCUCUACUCUAAAUUUUUUGUCCCGAAGCCCCCAAAUACUGCAACCCUGACCCAAUGCACGAAGCCACCCCAAAAUACAGCAGAGGACACCAGGACUUUCAUUUUCCCUCAGUAUGGCCCAUCCUUUGGGUAUGCCAACUCCAUGUCCACCAAGCACUGCAUGUAGGACAGGGCACAGUUUGGAGGCCUUGGUCCAGCCACUGCCCCAGACCCACCUUGGCUCUCUCCUCACUAACACCCGAGAAGCCCAGACUUCCCAGUGUUUAGCAACAGAUUAAACUCUAAGCCAACAACAACAGAACAGGGUGGAGUGAGUGGAAAGCAAAUGAAAUGUUAAAAAAAAAAAAAAAGCAAUACUUGCAUUCUCAUUAGUAGGAACAUGUGAGAUGAAGCAUGUUAUGUUAUUAGGCAUUCUCUUGAUUCGGUAAACACAAGCUGAAUAAAUUUAUAAAUAUCAGCAUUAAGCGAGAUUUAACGGGGAGCUGUUUAUCUUCUGCCUGUCAGGCAGGCGGCAACACUCUCCAUGUAUCACUCGCCAGCCGUGCAGUCCUCACUCUCUUGCCCAGGUAAGCUGGGGAAGAGCCUGCUGCCGCCCAGCUCUGGUUGUGGAAGGGCUGGCACCAAGGAGCUGCGAGCUUACCUCAACUCAUCUCACCUCACCAUGCCGGCUGCGAGGCGGCCCGUGCAGUCCGUGCGCAGGAGGUCACACUCCCAUGCUGCAUCCCAGCCCCUCCAGAAGCAGAGCAUGACCUGGGUGACUUUGAGGAUGCUAUUUAACCUCUCUAAGCUAAAGCUCCUCGACUGCAGCAUCAACAGAUCAGUGCCGACCUGUUAAGGCCGUCGAGAGCAUCAAAUGCUACUGUUCAGCAGGUGCCUGACACAUAGUAGGUCCACAAGCAAAUGAUUUUCCUGCUUGCAUCAUUUCUAGCACAGAGCUGGAGGAAAUGGCGAGGUGCAGGUGGCCGCUGGGCCCUGCUGUUCUACAUGGGAGCAAGACAGCUGCUAGGUGAAGGGGAAUGACCAGGCAGCCACAGGGAGGACAUGUGGCCUCAGGAAGCCUGGGUGUGUAUCCUGGUUCUGCUAGGAACACGUGUGGGGCUUUGUGUGGGUGACUCUCUGGCUCCCCAAGCCUCCCUUUCCUACUGUUAUAUCCUUAAAGUGCCUCUGAGGCCAAAGCCUUUGUGGCAAUUGUCAAAUGAGUCCAUAUGCAGUGAGUACCGUGUUGAGGGAGGACAAGGUCACCAAGAGCUGAGAAUGUUUCUCCGACUGAUGAGACCUAGAUAUUGGGUACAUGGAGGUCCCCGGUCCCUUUGUGAUUCCUGCAGCCUGUUGCCUCCUUGCCUGGACCCCGCCUCAGCUCAGAAAGCCAAUUCCCUAGAUUCCAAAGGCCUUCCCAGACCAAUUAGCAUGUCCUGCAGCUGUCAGCUCCCUGUGCCUAGCCUGGACCUCAGCUCAUGUCUAGCACCCAGUCUCCCAACCCCACACAUAUUCACAAAUAAAAGAAAAUAACAAAUGACAUGAAUUCUUCA